AGAGCCCAGCCCAGCACGGUCUCCGGGGAUGUAGCUGGUGGGACAGUGAGCAGAGGGCUGGGCCCUGUGCCUGGGGACUGUGGCCUGGAGGCUGAGCAGGAGCUGAGGAGGGGACCAGAGGGACAAGGCCCCUAAGCUGGCCACCAUGGCCAGACUCUGAGUGCAGGGGAGGUGAGGGGCCUGCGUGUGCCUUAUCUUCCCAGACACACUGGAUCCUUCUUGUCCUCUGAUCAAGGGAAAGACAAACGACCUGGAUGGACCACAACUUUGCUCCUGCUCCUCCAGAGAUGCAGUCGCAUGGAGCUCCAGGCCCGGGAACCUCCUUCUCCCAUAGCCAUGUGCUGGGGCGCCCUAUCCGCCCCUCGAGACUCCCUGGAGGAGGGUCCCCCCUCACCCCCGUCCUCAGGAAGACCAUCCAUCUGGAUACCUUCCCCCAAAGCCAUAUCCCACAGACCUCCAGCCGGCUGGGCCUUGGAGCCAGGACCCGGAGUGUGCCCCCACAGGAGACGGGCAUCGCUCUGGGGGCUUCCUUGAGCCCCCUGCCCACCAGCAGCCUUGUACCCAGGAAGCUCAGCUCCAUCUCCUUGACUCUCCAUCAGAACAGCCAGGCACGGUCCCUGGAUCGCCCACUUUCUCACUGGGAAGAGUUGCCUACCCCAGGAAAGAAGGCUGCUCCCCAUGAAGGAGGGAGGGUGUCCUCGCCAGGCUCGCCACCUGUGACCCUAGUGCCAGGGGGCAGGGUCCACUCUGAGGGCCCAGGGAACCCAGGUCUGACCAAAUCCAACAGGAUGCUUGCCACGGAGAAGCCCCUGGUGAGUUCCUACCUAGCCUUACCUUUCCAAUCCCGGUUAGCCCAGAGUGCACCAGUCCUUGCAGAGCCAGGCUCGUUGGGCCAGGGGCACCUUGUCUCAGUGACUGACCACAUGCCUACCAGAGCUUCUCCAGGAAAAGGCAAGCCCCGGGCCAGGGGGAUCCCCAGACCCCGGGGGCGUCUCCAAAGGGCCAACACGACUGUGAAUUUGACUGCUAUGGACACAAGGACAGACGCAGCCAGACAUUUAGCCACAAUGGCCACCAACAGACCUAGCUUGGCUAUCAAUUUAGCCACACCAAACACAUCCCAACUGGACACAGGCACAGAGUUCCCUGCCCUGGAUAUCAAGCUGGGCACAGCCAGAGACUUGUCUUCGGUAGGGACAGUCAAGUCAGGCAAAACCGUGAACUUGGCUACAGCAGGCACAAUCAAGCCGGGCACAGCCAUGAAUCUGACUACAGUUGGGACAACCAAGCCAGGGAUGGUCAUGGAUUUGAUAGCCUCAGAACCAGACAAGCUGGGCAAAGCCAUGGCUACAAGAAGCACAGCCAAACCAGAUAUGACCACAGAGGGUAUAGCCAUGGAUUCAGCAACAUCAGACCCAGUCAAGCCGGACACAAUCACAGCUACAGUGGGCACCAGUAGGUUGGAAACAGCCAUGGCUUUGGCCAGAGUGAACAGAGCCAAGCUGGGCACGGCUAAGAAUUCUCUUGCUUUGGACACAAGCAGGAUGGGCACAGCUGUGGGUUCAGUUGUGCCAGUAACCCCAGACCCAGCCACUGGGAAGACCACACUGGGCAGUGUUAAUAACCUAACCAUAUCAGACGUUGCUACAUGCCUGCUAAUGCCAAGCAGAUCCACAGACCUAGCCCUGGACAACACUAAUGCUGCCAUGGACAGAGCCACAGAGCCUGCCUCACUGGACCUGGCCACAGAAUACAAAGGGCUCCCAGAGACCAGGACGGACGCAGCCAUGUCAGAGCUGGUGCCUGAGCCCAGGCCUAAGCCAGCGGUGCCCAUGAAGCCCAUGAGCAUCAACUCCAACCUGCUGGGCUACAUCGGCAUCGACACCAUCAUCGAGCAGAUGCGCAAGAAGACCAUGAAGACCGGUUUCGACUUCAACAUCAUGGUCGUUGGCCAGAGUGGACUGGGCAAAUCAACGCUGGUCAACACGCUCUUCAAAUCCCAAGUGAGCCGCAAGGCCUCCAGCUGGAACCGGGAGGAGAAGAUCCCCAAGACAGUGGAGAUCAAAGCUAUCGGGCAUGUGAUAGAGGAAGGCGGUGUCAAAAUGAAGCUGACCGUCAUCGACACCCCAGGCUUUGGAGACCAAAUCAACAAUGAAAACUGCUGGGAGCCCAUUGAGAAGUACAUCAAUGAGCAGUACGAGAAGUUCCUGAAGGAGGAGGUCAACAUCGCCAGGAAGAAACGCAUCCCUGACACUCGUGUCCACUGCUGCCUUUACUUCAUCUCUCCCACAGGACACUCCUUGCGACCUCUGGAUCUUGAGUUCAUGAAACACCUCAGCAAGGUUGUGAACAUCAUCCCUGUCAUUGCUAAGGCUGACACCAUGACCCUGGAGGAGAAGUCUGAAUUCAAGCAAAGGGUUCGCAAGGAGCUUGAAGUAAAUGGCAUUGAAUUCUACCCCCAGAAGGAAUUUGAUGAGGAUUUGGAGGAUAAGACGGAGAAUGACAAAAUCAGGCAGGAGAGCAUGCCUUUUGCUGUGGUGGGAAGUGACAAGGAGUACCAAGUGAAUGGCAAGAGGGUCCUCGGCCGAAAAACUCCAUGGGGGAUCAUCGAAGUGGAAAACCUCAACCACUGUGAGUUUGCCCUGCUUCGAGACUUUGUCAUCAGGACCCACCUCCAGGACCUCAAGGAAGUGACACACAACAUCCACUAUGAGACUUACAGGGCCAAGCGGCUCAAUGACAAUGGAGGCCUCCCUCCGGUGAGCGUGGACACAGAGGAAAGCCACGACAGUAACCCAUGACGACCACUUCUCUGUGUCAUCACACAUACCCACUUCACACACACACAUCCCAAAUACCACCACCAACCACCUUCUUCCUCUCAACUCUGUCCCACAGGCCUGUCUGGUAUUUGUGGAGCAUCUUGUCUGUGUGUGUGUGUGUGUGUGUGUGUGUGUGUGUGUGUGUGACAGAGAGAGAGCGAGAGAGCCUGUGUGUGUGCAUGCAGGGGUGAGGUAUUUUCACUGCCCUCCCUGGAGAGUCCCUUGUAAGUUUGGCUCCUCCAUGCCUGUCCAUUAUCUGUCUCCUUUCCUUGUGUCCCAAAACAAAGCUGUUUGCCUCACUCAGGAGAUCUGGGGGAGGUUUCAUUUAAAAGUGCUGGGAGCAGGUGAGCCACAGGCAACUCUUCUCUCGGAACCUGCACACAAACUGGGGCUAUAGAGAUUCUCCAAGGACAGAUGGCAGUGGAGCUAGACCUGAGUAGGGGGCAGGGAGUUCAGGACAACCCUCCUGUAAGUUGGGGGUGGUCUGGGGGUAAGGCUGGGGCUUCCUGGGAAAAGGAAGGCCAUGAGAAGGCAGAGAAGUAGGCCAGAGCUGGGUUCUUGCAGAAAGCAUCAGUGCCUACAAAUGGAGCUCCACCCUUCAGUCUGUGUCGUGUUCAGUGUCACAAAGCUACCACCUGUCACCAGAGCCUACUGCUGCUCUCCACUCAACUGGCCUCUGCUGCCAGGCCACUGCCUGUCUCUGCUUCCGACUUUGUCUUCUUUCUCCCUUUCCCUCCUUCCCUCAUACAUUGCUUUCUCUCCCUCUCCUGCGUGUCUCUGACAUCUCUCACUUCCUUUUAGAUGAAUCUACUUUAGGUUCAUUCCUAUAUUUAGCAUUUAUGCCCAGUCUACUUCCAGAAAUGACUUUAGACUGCCUUUCACAUAAAAUCACAAAACUACAGGACAGUACAAACAGAUUGCCAGAGAAAUCUGGGUCAAAGAAAGGAAUAGGAAAGAAAGUUUCUGUAGUCAAGCACCUGAACAGGCCCUGAGCUCACAGGCAGCCAAUGUAAAGAGGGAAACACAGUGAGUUAUGCAGUUCCCAGUGUCCAGUUAAAGGAAGCACACAUGCUAGUCAUGUGAGACAACCUUUUAUUGGGACAUCAGGUUCUAGAACUAAUUCUAAAGAAGUAUCAGAAACAAUAUACAUAAUUUGUCUUUCUUAGUAAUUUGGCUUCAAAGACAAAUUUUUGACCACACCUCCGUUUUCUCCGUCAGACUUCUCUCCCUUCUAAGCAGGCUUCUCUGUUGCUCCAUUUGCUUCAUACAUACUUGACCUCUCUUUUCUAUUCCCCAUCACUUUUGUGCUGAAGCUAAUCAUAUUUAUGUCUGUCUUUCUCUACUUUUCCCUAAUUCCCUCUCCUCCUGACUCCUGUAGACAUUCCCAAUGAUACCCACCGUCAUACAUUUAGGCUUUUCUUGCCUUUCCCUGAAGCCCUGUAUUUAUUAAUGCAUAUAUUUCCCCUGCUUGUUGUACAAGUAAGUUACUCUUUUCCUUUAAUCUGUAAGAUUCAUGAAAUUCGGGGCCAGGGAAACAGUUUAGCCUUAGGGAAGGGAAAACACUAAGUGAAACUGUUUACAAUAACCUCAUACAACCUUCUGUCCCAUCUCCUGGUUCAGCCUAGGUGUUUCACUGGUCCUCUAUGAAUCCCAGCACUUAUAAUCCCAGUCUUUUAUCACUCAGGUGCUAGGAAAAAAAACAUAGACUCAAGACCCAAGAUUCAAUGGACCAGGAGAAAGGGGGGCGGUGAUCAGGUCACCAGUGACCCCAACCUAUGCUCUCGGUCUUUCCUGGAGGCUGCCAACCCAGCCCUCAUCCUCCCUUGCUCACAAAGUUACAGGGUAGGCACCUGUCAGGACAGAACAGCAGCAGCGCUACAGCCCAGAGGUUAUACAUUUCAACAGAACAGGGAUCCUUGGCUACUGUAGAAGCAGUCCUGUAUGGAGACCUUGGACCAGCAGGGGAAGAUCUAUGGGCAUGGGAGGUGGGCGUUGGAAAGGCUGAGUAGGAAUGGUGCCUGGCACCCCUGAACCAUGAUCUGAGCCUCCCUGGAGAAGGUAUUUUAUAUGUCUGCUGCCAGCUGCUGGUCUCCACACCCUCAACCGUUCUCAACCCCCCUGCAGGGAGAAGGCCUCCUGGGCACUGUCCUUCCACCUGUGCCAGCCACCCCCUGCCCCACUGCUGAAUGAAGGCCAUUUCAAGCGCUGCUUCUCACUCCAUUCCUCUCAGCUGUUAUUGCUGCAGGGCCAAGCCCUUUUUAGUGCUGUGCUCGUCCAGCUCACCACCACAGCCCCUCUCAGCCCUCAGUAGGUGGGAGGGGCCAGCUGCCUCUUUAGGCCAGUUGCAUCCUCCAUUUAUCCAAACCACUCCUCUCCUCCCAGUGGAGUGGGGUUCUGCCAGUACAGCCCUACUGCAUCAUCUGCGUCAGCCGGUCCUAGCCCAUCUGCAGGGUGAAAGAACUCAUCAAGAGCUCCUUCUGCCCUUGUAAGCCCAUCCCAGCUACUUGUAACCAUCUCUAAGGGCAAUGGCAUUGCUCCCUACCCAUUCAUCUGCAUGAGCUACUCUUGGCUUCCUUAAAGGGUCAAGAAAGCAAUUUUUCUGCUUACUAGAUUCAUUGAGAUCAGCUGUGUGAGCCCCAAAGUGGGACAAGGGUGUCUCCUUCAUUACUUAAAGAUAUUCAUGAGGGUGGGUCACUACAGAUGUUGGGGAGCAAGGGCUAGGAUCACUUUUUAAAAAAUCACCACUUGUGGCUGUCCCAGAGUGCGGUUGUACAUCCUCCCCACCUCAUAACGCAGCCACUGAGGAAGAGUGGUUUUCCUAAGAAGACAUUGCUGGAGUUGACUUUCUUCUGUCCAAACAAACAAACAAAAACUAAACACACACACAAACCCCCAGAAACCCACAAUAUGUACACGCUAAGGAAAAACUAGCACCCUUCUGUCCACUCAGCAAUAAGAGGGAUCUCUUCCCACCUACCCUACCUACUCCUACCCCCAACCCCCUUCCCCAUUAAUGUGAGUAAUGAAUUAGCCUGACCACAGGUGGUCACUGUAGGCUAAUGGAAAAUACCCAAGGGAGGGCAAAGCCCCCCAUCAGAUGCAUGAAUGUUUGCGAAUGUUGACUGCCACUGCCCCACACACUGUGUCUUUAUAGAAUUCCCCUUUGCCCACCCUCUUCCUGUCUCCACCUGGACACAACUUGCUCAAAGGCUGGUGACUUGUGGGCCAUUCAUCUACAACCAAGUCCUGAUGGAGCAAGAGGCCCACGCCUAGGGGAUGCAAGAACAACCCGUUUCUUAAAUGUUACCAGUCCCAGCCAAUCUUACGGUGACAUUACAGUUAAAUUUCCCAAUUGAAAACAAGCAAACAGACACUCAAACUGGUCCUGUAAUUGUUGCUAGACUUUAUGUGUUGUACAACUAAACAUUGCUGUUUGAACAGUAA